GGUAAUAUGGCUCUUCCUUAGCCAGCGGCGGCAACGGCGGCAGCGGCGGCAGCGGCGGCGGCUACUGUCUGGGCUGAGCAGUAGUGCCUCUCGGGUGGCGGGUUUCUAGGCUGCAGGGGCUUGGUAGGUGGUGGCAAGGGGGCGGCGGCGGAUGCCGGAAGAGUGCCCGCCCCGCCGCUUGGCGGCCCCUGGAUCGAGAUGAGCGCCUCCGCGUCGGUCGGGGGCCCCGUCCCCCAGCCACCCCCGGGCCCGGCCGCUGCUCUGCCUCCCGGUUCUGCCGCGCGGGCCCUGCAUGUGGAGCUGCCGUCUCAGCAGCGGCGUCUUCGACAUCUUCGGAACAUUGCUGCCCGGAACAUUGUUAAUAGAAAUGGCCAUCAGCUCCUUGAUACCUACUUUACACUUCACUUGUGUAGUACUGAAAAGAUAUAUAAAGAAUUUUAUAGAAGUGAAGUGAUUAAGAAUUCCUUGAAUCCCACGUGGCGAAGUCUCGAUUUUGGAAUUAUGCCAGACCGUCUUGAUACAUCUGUGUCUUGUUUCGUGGUGAAGAUAUGGGGUGGAAAGGAGAACAUCUACCAGCUGUUGAUUGAAUGGAAAGUCUGUUUGGAUGGGCUGAAAUACUUGGGUCAGCAGAUUCAUGCCCGAAACCAAAAUGAAAUAAUUUUUGGGCUGAAUGAUGGAUACUAUGGUGCUCCAUUUGAACAUAAGGGUUAUUCAAAUGCUCAGAAGACUAUUCUUCUGCAGGUGGAUCAGAACUGUGUUCGCAAUUCUUACGAUGUCUUCUCUUUGCUACGGCUUCAUAGAGCCCAGUGUGCAAUUAAACAGACUCAGGUAACUGUUCAGAAAAUUGGAAAGGAAAUUGAAGAAAAACUAAGACUCACAUCUACAAGCAAUGAACUGAAAAAAAAAAGUGAAUGCCUGCAGUUAAAAAUUUUGGUGCUUCAGAAUGAACUGGAACGGCAGAAGAAAGCUUUGGGACGGGAGGUGGCAUUACUGCAUAAGCAACAAAUUGCAUUACAAGACAAAGGAAGUGCAUUUUCAGCUGAGCACCUCAAACUUCAACUCCAGAAGGAAUCCCUAAAUGAGCUGAGGAAGGAGUGCACUGCAAAAAGAGAACUCUUCUUGAAGACUAAUGCUCAGUUGACAAUUCGUUGCAGGCAGUUACUCUCUGAGCUUUCCUACAUUUACCCUAUUGAUUUGAAUGAACAUAAGGAUUACUUUGUAUGCGGUGUCAAGUUGCCUAAUUCUGAGGACUUCCAAGCAAAAGAUGAUGGAAGCAUUGCUGUUGCCCUUGGUUAUACUGCACAUCUGGUCUCCAUGAUUUCCUUUUUCCUACAAGUGCCCCUCAGAUAUCCUAUAAUUCAUAAGGGGUCUAGAUCAACAAUCAAAGACAAUAUCAAUGACAAACUGACGGAAAAGGAGAGAGAGUUUCCACUGUAUCCAAAAGGAGGGGAGAAGUUGCAGUUUGAUUAUGGUGUCUAUCUUCUGAACAAAAAUAUAGCACAGAUGGAGUCUUGCUGUGUCACCCAGGCUGGAGUGCAAUGGCGCGAUCUCGGCUCACUGCAACCUCUACCUCCCGGGUUCAAGUGAUUCUCUUGCCUCAGCCUCCCAAGUAGGUGGGAUUACAGGCGCAUGCCACCACGCUCAGCUAAUGUUUUGUGUUUUUAGUAGAGACGGGGUUUCACCGUGUUAGGCAGAUGGUCUCGAUCUGCUGACCUCGUGAUCCGCCUGCCUCAGCCUCCCAAAGUGCUGGGAUUACAGGUGUGAGCCUUUAAAACACCCAGCCUAUUUAUUUUUAUAAAUAACAAGUGUUUUGUUUUGUUUUCAUUGGACAUCCUUCCAACUGGAAUAUCACAUGGAUGAGUAUCCACAAUUUGGCUUUUAUUUAAAUACAUUGUGAGCUAUAUCCUCAGACCUUUUGGUUUUACCAAAGUAAUAAGAUUUACGAUGCUUUUGUUUUUGUUGGCCUGUGUUGCCAUUUAUCCACAUGAACCUAACGACUUGCUAAACAUUCCCUUAUUCAUUUCUGAUCAGUCUAGAAUUAUUCCUCUAUGUGGUGUCAUCUGCCACUCUUCCCCUUAACCAACCUCAGUUUAAUGGUGGAGAUUUUUUUAAUUUGUUUUUUAUUAAGAUUGUUGUUCUCUUCUGAAAUUGGGUCAGAUUUCUGGAUUGCAAUCCUCAGUUUAUCAUUUGCUUCAUCCUUCACACUCAUUGUCCUCUCAACCAUACUACUUUUACUGUUACUUCCACUCCAGCUCCAGGAAAGCAGCCCUCUGACAGUCUCUGGCCCAUGACUCACCUUUCCAUGUGCCAUUCUUCCCACAACUGAUGCUUGCCCAUUCUGCAUUUUUGGCAGACAAGUAUUUCAUUCAAAGAAGCAGGGCUUUAAUUCCAAGACUGCCGAGCUCCCACUCCGCUGAUCACAGUUCUGUCAUGCCAUGGAAAAGGCAGUGCUUAAACAGAACUUGUCAAAAGUGCUCAGACUGAGGCCAGGUGUGGUGGCUCAUGCCUGUAAUCCCGGUACUUUGGGAGGCCGAGAUGGGUGGAUCGCUUGUGGCCAGGAGUUGGAGACCAGCCUGGGCAACAUGGCAAAACCCCAUCUCUACUAAAAAAUACAAAAAUUAGCCAGGUGUGGUGGCAUGCACCUGUAAUCCCAGCUACUGGAGAGGCUGAGGCAUGAGAACCUCUUGAACCCGGGAGGCAGAAGUUGCAGUGAGCUGAGAUCGUGCCAGUGCACUUCCAGCCUGGGUGACAGAGCAAGAUUCUGUCUCAAAAAAAAAAAAGUGCUCGGACUAAGACUGCACUAAGGAAGAAGUAAAUUAGAGGGCUCCUCCAGCGAUGUCAGCCGUGGUGGAAAGAGCAUGUAGAUACUACAGGAUCCAGUUUGAGAGUAAAACUGGCAUCAUUUAGUAGAACUAAGUUCUGAUUUGAGUUCAGAACUUCUCUUCUUGCCCUAUUUUCUCUUUCUUGCUCUAGGCACUUAGAUCCUAAGGUCAGAAGGCUAUUGGAAGCUUCCUGGUGAAACUUACUCCUGCUGAAAUGCCUGUAUUUCCUCAUAUAUUCCAGCUUCAAACAUACACACAAUAUGCACAUGUGUACAGAUAUACACACACAUGCACAAACACACUUCUUUCUUCUCAAGGGCCCAAAAGGAUGGUAUGCCAAAAGAUCAUAUAAAGUGUUGCUAAGAAUACCACAGCUUGCUUUGGGAGCAAGACCAAGAUGGAGGCUAUGUGCAGGGGAAAACUUAGCAAAGUCAGCCCUCCUCAUCAGACUCUCAACUCUAGGGCCUGUUUGAUCCCCACUUCCCAAGAGGCCUCUGACUUUAUUAUUAACUGAACCAGGGCCACAAGUAUGCUGACCUAGUUUUACUCAUCUGAGAAAUGGAUUGCUUGUAGUAAUUGUGUAUCCUCUCCAGCUUUAUAUAUGCUCUUUGAAAAUUGAGAGAACAAUCAAUAGGUUAACUACUCUGAAUCCAUAGGGAGCAAGUAUCCUCCUCUGUGGAUUUUCUUUUUUUAAUCACACUGGAGGCAGUUUUAAAAGGAGGGGACAGUAAACUUCUUAAAAACUGGCUUUUUUAUAUUUCAAAAUGUAUUCGGGAAGCCCUUUAAGCAGUUAGAAACUUUUAGAACAGUUGUGACCUUUCACUUUUUUUGCUUCAGCUCUGUCUGUUCUGUCUCUCGCUGUUUCUCAGGGAAGCUUUCAUUUUGUCUUUGACCUUACUGCCAUCACUUUUUCACGUUUUGAUUUGUAACAAAUGAAAGAACCAUUAAUUGUUAUGGCUCCUAAGCGAGCAUUGUAGCAAUCAGGUAUUUCCAGCUUUUGAAGGUUUAUUUUUAUAGACAUAUAGACUAAUAUAUGUUGUCAAAGGGGAGUUUGUCUUCUCAGCCAGUUCCAUAUGUACCCAUCUUUUAAGAUGUGAACAAAUCAUACUAUUAAAAUGGCCUCACCUCAGUAAUUUAUAAGCCACAUUAGUGGAGGUGGAUGAAAGCAUUGGCAUGUGUUAAAGUGCCAGAGAAAAAGGAGUGAAGUCAUUUAAUACUGCAUCCAUAACUUGGUUGAGGAUUUGAAUAGUCAAUAGGACCUUUCAUCACAACCAGAAGUAGUAGUAAAAUCACUUUUUUGGUAGAGGAAAUGACAGAAUUUAGUAAUAUUUGUUACUUCAGUAUUUGGGAUCAGUCCAGCCCAAGUUUUGAAAGCACAAGCUUAGAGAGACAGGCCUUCAAGUAGAAAUCCUCAAGUGUUGUUUGAAGAGCUGAGAGCACUGGUAAGGCCUGCUUGCCCUCUUCAUGUCACUGCUGUCUAAAGGUGUGUGUGUGUGCUGGAUUAAGUACUGAGAGUGAGUGAAGCAAAAUGCCUUGUUUUCAGCACCAUAUAUUAAUAUUUGUUAAGUGCCAGCCUCUUCAGUUAGAAAUAGCCUUCCUUCUUGGCUAGCAUGUAAUGCUAUAGGAAUGGGCCUGUCAAAAUUCAGGUGCAGUAUAAUUGACGUUGACUUUAAAAACCAGAUCCUGCCAUAAUUUCAGUUAGUUCAUAAGUACAUUAUAUUAGAAUUUGUAUAGAGAACAGAAAUUUGCUUUUAAUUCUCAGAGCAUAAAAAUUAAAUGGAAAACAAAAAUUAUAAUACUUUUAUCUUAUAUUUGUGGGAGCCUUAUAGUUUGUAAAGUACAUGCAUAUAAAUUCACAUGAUCCCUAUCAUCACCCUGCAAAGUAAAAAGGGCAGAUGCUAUUAAAUCGAUUUGAGGACAGCUUGGCUUUUGACAUUUGUCCCUCCAGUGUCAUAUCACAUAAUUUGAUAAGUGUGGCAGAGAUCCCCUUACUUCUAUAUACUUCACUGUUCUAUAUAUUUCCAUCCUUAAAGUGCACCAAAUCAAAGAAGACGACAUUCCCAGAUAGAAAAGGAAGCAAACGUUUUUUGAGAAUGGAGACAAAAACUAUUUUGCACAUCAUAAUUUUUCCAUUAGCAAGCACAAUGCCAGAAACACUGUAAGUUCUAAAGAAAUUAAUAAUGAAUGGUGAUAUAGCACCAUCACACAAGAAACUAAGAUCUAGAAAAGUUAAGUGACUUUAAUGAAUUUUAAAAAUUGUGAUACACAAACACAACGCACACACACACAAAUAGAAUAUUAUUCAGCCUCUGUAAAGGACAUACUGCCAUUUGUGACAAUACAGAUGAACCUGGAGGAUAUUAUGCUAAGUGAAAUAAGCCAGACACUGAAAGACAAAGACUGUAUGAUCUCAGUCAUAUGCAGAAUCUUAAAUGUAAAAGUUGAAUAACUAGAAACAGAGAGUAGGAUAGUGAUUCAGUGGGAGGGAGAGGAGGAAAUAGGAAGAAGCAGGCUAAAGGGUAUACAAAUUUGCAGUUAGAUAGGCUGCAUAAGUCUAGGGAUAUAAUAUACAGAAUGAGGAUUAUAGUUAGUAAUAUUGUAUUGUGUACUGAAAAUUUGUCAAGAGAGUAGAUUUCUACAGUUUUUAUCACACACACCCAUGAAUAUGUUAAUUUGUUUGACUGCUAUAAUCAUUUCACUAUGUAUAUGUAUAUCAAAACAUCAUGUAUACCUUCAAACAUCUUGUACCCCUUAAAUUGAUACAAUAUAAAAUUUUUUUAAAGUUAGGUGACUUGCUUAUAAUUCAUUAGUUUAUUCAACAGUAUUUGUUGAGCAUGUACUGUGUGCUGUGUACGCUGAGUUAGGUUGCAGUGGGUAGAGCAAUGAAUAAGAUACACUAGAUCCCUGAUCCCUGCCUCGUUAAUAUGCUAGACACAAAAGGACAAAUAUUGUAGCGUUCCAUUUAUAUAAGUAUCUACAAAAAGCAAACUCAUGGAGUCAGAAAGCCACAUUAGAGGGCUGGGGGAAUAGGAGAGCUAUAUUGCUUAAUGAUUACAGUUUCCGUUGGGGUGAUGAAAAAGUUUUGGAAAUAGGUGGUGACAACCAUUAUAUAUCAUUGUGUAUGUAAUCAAUGUCACUGAAUUUUACACUUAAACAUGGUUUAAAUGGCAAAUUUGAGUUGUACACUUUAAAUGGGUGAAUUGUAUGUUAUGUGAAUCAUAUCUCAAUAAAGCUGUUUUAAUAAAAGAAAAA